AUGGCCCCGUGGAGCCGAGAGGCGGUGCUGAGUCUCUAUCGGGCUCUGUUGCGCCAGGGCCGACAGCUUCGCUACACUGAUCGAGACUUCUACUUUGCCUCCAUCCGCCGUGAAUUCCGAAAAAAUCAGAAGCUAGAGGACGCUGAGGCCCGGGAGAGGCAGCUGGAGAAGGGCCUGGUCUUUCUCAACGGCAAAUUGGGGAGGAUCAUUUAG